GUUCUAUUGGAUGUUGGAACUCUUGGGUUGCUUGUCUGAUUUUCGCUCUGUUUUCUAAAAGAUUUCCUCAGGUUUCUCUUUACCUUUUUCCUUUGAAUUCUUUUUUUCUGCUAUUAUGAUAUUUAGUUUACAAGAGCUUUUUCUUGUUCUCUUUUCCUUUCUUGAUAGCAUUUUGUCUAUGGGUGUAAUAGGUUUUUUUGUUUGUUUUUCUGAAAUAUUAAAAAGUAGAUUGCUUGUCUUCUGGUGGACUUCACUUAAGGAUGCUUGGGCAAGCUGGCGUUUUCCUUAGGGAUACCUCCAAAUAUCAGUAUCUGGAGGUUGUUCUUAUUUAGUUUUCUGAAGAAGAAUUCUCAUUUUCCCCCUACGGCAGGUAGGUGCUUAUCUUACAAAGUUAUAGAGGCAGAUUAGAUAAAGACUUUUGGGCUUUAUUCAGUACAGGCUUUUUAGCCCUGUACCUGGUGUUUCUGAAUCUAGAGUCAGUUGCUCCAAAGAAUACAUCUGUGGUCCUCUUGAAUUCAGAAAGGUUAUUAUAGCUGCAGUAUAGUGAUUAAAUUGUGAUAGAAUGAAAUGAAUUCAAGAGAUCAUUAGGAAGGGUUACAGAGGUCCAAGAAAAAGAUGUUAGUAGCUUAGAGAUAAUGGAGAUGAAGGAAAACAGAUUGAUUUGAGAUUUAGAUGGAAAUUUGACUUAUCUCUCUAUAGCUGUAUUUACUGCUUGCUAAUUAGAUGAUAGGUCUAACAAGCAGAGACUAUGUCUCCACUAUUUGUAUAUUCUGCAGCACCUGGUGCCCAGCAAGAUUUGGUGUCUAUUGAAUGGUACUCAGCAUGUUAAUGAUUUAAUGAGAUUAUUAUGACUUAGAUUUCUUACAAUCUUCACUGUUUAAUCUAUCAUUUAAAAAUCACAUGAUUUGGUUGAGACAUUGGCUAUGAUCAAAGUAUUUGUUUACUGAUUUUUAAAAUUUGCGUAUAUAUUUACCGUAUUGACCUCCAUCUGGCAUAAAAGAUUUAUGGGUGCCAUUAGAGUAGUAAGAUUGAAGCUAUUGUUAGAUGUAGGUAUUUGGUGAGUUUUACUCAUAUCUGCUCUGAAUUUUGUGUAUAGAUUUCUACUUUGCUAGUUAGUGUAAAAGUUAUUUUGGGACAAAUAACCUCAUCAACAAUUAUAACAGAUUUUCUAGAUUUAUCAUCAUUAGAUUUACGUAGUAAGAGCUAUAUUGUCACAUUCAUUAUGGUAUCUUGAUAAAAAUAAGUUCUUAAUUUAAAUGUAGUUUAAAUUAUCAAUCUUUUAUGGUUCCUACUUUGGCGGCUUGUUCAAGAAAUCCUCUCUUGGAGGAUUCAAGAAGAUAUUUCUUUAUAUAUUUAACUGAGUGUUUUAAAUAUUUUGCUUUUAACAUUCAAGUCUUUAAUCCAUCUGGAAUUGGUGGUAUGAGGUAGACAUCAAUAAAAUUUUAUUUUAUUCCAUCUUGAAAAUCACUUGUGUGUUACACUAUUACCUGAUUUCUGUGGUGCUACUUCUGAAGCACAUUGUAAUUCCAAAGAUGCAUGUAACUCCAUAUGUCUCUGAUCUUUAUAUUCUAUUCCAUUUGUCAGUCUAUUUCUGCACCAAAUUCCACACACUGUCUUAAUUAUGACAGUUUUAAGAUAAAGCUUGAUAUCUGAUUGUACAAUACUUCCACAGUAUCCUUCCUUUUCAGGAGUGUUUUGGCUAUACUUGGCUCUUUAGUCCUCCAUAUGAAAUUCAGAAUCAGCUUUUCAAAGUCCAUACACAGUCUUGUUGGGAAGUUGGGAGUUGCAUUGGUAGAGAAAAUUGACAUCUUUACAAUAUCUAGUUUUCCUGCCUGUGAAUAUGGGAUAUUCUUGCAUUUGUAUUUAUCUUCUUUAAUAUUUGGGGAUCUUUAUAGUUUUUUGCGUACAGGUUGUGGUACAUUGUACUUUCUAAAGAUACCCACAAAAAUAUCCCCCAUCCCACAUGGCCUUCUACAUUAUGACCUUGCUACUCCCCCACCAAUAGGUGGAGUCUAAUUUCCCUUCUCUUGAAUCUGGGCAGAAGUAAAGCUGCUUAUUUGUUGACUUGCUAGUUUAAUUUAAAACACAUUGUAAUUGCAUUAUUUUCCCCAUUUUUGUCACUUACCAUACAAAAGUAUAAAAGGAAUAUUUUACAAAGCUUCAUCUUCCUCAGCUCUUCUUCCCAAAUACUUAAUAUUUAGUAACAAUACUAAUUGAUAAUAGAGGAUUCUGAAAAGUACAUCACAGUUUCUACCUUGAAGGAACUUACAUAGACAGGAAUUCACAAAAAGUUAAAUUAAGUAUUUAAACAAUAGUUUAAAACCUUAGUAAAAGUUAAUGUAAGUCAGAAUAUGAUUAAUUGACAAUUGCAUUAUAGAGACCAAUAAAUGAUAUAGUACCUGCUAUCUGGAUGCUGGAUAAGGGGGUAUUAUCCUCAUUUUUCAGAUACCAGAAAGCUGAAGAGAUUUAGUGUUUGUCUAAGAAGUAGUAGGAAACCAGUUUAUCUGGCAUAGUGUCAGUGCUCUUAGUUGGCACUUCAUAAGAAUCUUUAAUGAGAACCCAUUCCAGUGUUGUAUUCUAGUGUUUUUAGUUUAAUCUGGAAACAUUUUGAAUAAUAAUUCAGGUGGAUAGGGAUUCGAGUGCUACACUUAAUACCUGUAUAAGAUGCUCAUUAGAUAUUUGUUAAAUAAAUGGAGACCUUUUUCUCUAUUGAUUUUUACUCUUUUUGGUGGCUUAGUUAAUACUUGUUAAGCUAUAUAUAUUCUUUCUGGUGACUUUUGAUGUUGAAAUAAGUGAGAAGUCAUUAUAUUAGUAUCAGUGCCUUAAGUAUAGUAGUUAGGUAAUGAAAGAAUAGUCCAGAUUUAUUUUAAUUAAAUAGCUAUGACUCUGGAGCCCUUAGCAAUAAAUUAUAUGCUGUCUAGAAUGUGUUUACUCUAAGUUAUUUAAAUGUUUACCAGUGGACUUCUGCUCUGUGUUUGUAAAGAAAUCAGAUUAAUUAUUAUGAUACCAAAUGUUUUCUGCUGUACACAAUUUGUUCUCAAAAUUACAUGUUGUAAAAACACAUUAAGAAUCCUUAAAUCAAUAUUUUAAAAAUGCAAAUAUAUGCAUAGCCACUCUUAAUCAUUAAAUACAUAAUUAGCCAUUUUUCAGAAUUUUCAAUUAACUUAAAAUAAUUACUUUUUACAAUUAUCAGUAUAGAUAAGUAUAUAUUUGAAUUUUUUUUAAUCUUUAGACAGAAGUUUUGGGACAUUACUGAAAGAAGGAAAAAAGCCAUAAGUACUUAUAACAUUUAGUUAUAAAACCAAAGAGAACAAAAGAGAGAAGUUGUUUUUAAUUUAUUAAAAGUGUAGGCUGGGCGCAGUGGCUCACACCUGUAAUCCCAGCACUUUGGAAAGCUGAAGCGGGCAGAUCACGAGGUCAGGAGAUCGAGACCAUCCUGGCUAACACAGUGAAACCCCGUCUCUACUAAAAAUACAAAAAAUUAGCCGGAUGUGGUGGUGGGCACCUGUAGUCCCAGCUACUCGGGAGGCUGAGGCAGGAGAAUGGCGUGAACCCAGGAGGAGGAGCUUGCAGUGAGCCGAGAUCACACCACUGUACUCCAGCCUGGGUGACAGAGCGACACUCCAUCUCAAAAAAAAAAAAAAAAAAAGAAAAAGUGUAGCUAUAGUUUACAGUUUACUAUCUGUACACUGCAAAGCUUGUUAAGUUGAUAUAUGUUCUUUUUUAAAAACUUAUGUCAGUGAUUAUAGACCCCUUGAUUAACUGCUGGAUAUUUCUGAAAAUUUUCAGAAUUUGGUACAAUACCUGCUUUUCUGACCUGAUUAUUAGAAAAGCAGAAGCAUUUGAACAUUUGCUGUGUUCUAGAUACUCUUCUAGACACUGGGCAUACAUCUGUGGCGGUGGCAAGUGGAGAGAGCAGAGAGAGAUUUUUUUAAAGUAAACAAACAUGUAAUAUGUUAGAUGAUUAUAAGUGCCAUGAAGAAAAGUAAAGCAGGUUAAAGGCAACAAAGAAUCACAGAAGGUGUUGAGUGUUCUUUUAAAUAAAUGGUGUUUGUGGAAGGCUUCUGAUGACAUUUGAGCAGAGAUCUAAAGGAAGUGAAGGCAUAAACCAUGGGGAAUAGAAUUUUCCAGGCAGAGGGACGACUCUGAGGUGAGAGGAUGUGGCAUAGUCAAGAAAUAGUAAGGAACAGUAAGGAGGUCAGUGUGGCUAGUGUGAGCAAGGAGAGUACAGGAGAUGAAGUCAAAGAGAUCAGAGGGUCAGAUCAUGGAGAGCCUUGCAGGAUAUGGUAACUUAGAGUUAGUAGGCAGCUUUUGGAAGGCUCUGAGCUUCUUCCACUCUGCAUAAAUACUUUGAAAUUCAUUUAUGUUGUAAUGUCUGUCAGUGUUUAAUUCCUUUUUAUUAUUGAAUAGUAUUCUAUUGUAUGGCUAUACCACUAUACCACUGUUUGGCUAUUACUAAUAAAGCUGCUAUGAACAUUUGGGUACAGGUAUUUGUGUGGACAAAGGAUUUCAUUUAUUGUGGGUAAAUAGUUAGGAGUGGAAUGGCUGGAACAUAUAGUAGUUGUUUUUUAGGAAACUGCCAAGUUGUUUUCCAAAAUGAUUGUAUCGUUUUAUAUUCCCACCAGUUCCUCCAUUGUCCUUGCAAACAGUUGAUAUAGUCAGCCUUUUAAAUUUUCACCCUUCUAAUUAAGUCUGUAAUGGUAUCUCAUGAGUUUAACCUUCAUUUGCUUAAUGAUUAAUGAUGUUUCUGUUUUCUUUUGAAUUUUGAAUUUUAAUAAAUUAAAAACAACUUCUCUUGUUCUCUUUGAUUUUAUAACUAAAUGUUAUAACUGCUUAUGGCUUUUUUCCUUCUUUCAUGAAUUUUUUAUUCCAUUUUAUCUCCUUGCCUUGCUAGCUAAUACCUCUUUUAGUGGUUCCUUUAGGGUCUUUAGUGUACAUCUUAUCACAGUUUAUUUGCAAGUGGUAUUAUUCUAUUUCACAUAUGUUUAAGAAACUUAACAAUACACCUAUAUUUCUCCUCUACCAGCCUAUAUGCUGUUGUUCUCAUAUAUUUAACUUUUAUACAUCAUAUACUUCAUAAUAUUUAAAUAGGCAUUUAUUUUUUAAGUGAUUUAGAUAUUAAAGAAAAAAAUCUUAUAUAUGUACUGGUGUCAUUUCCAUUUUUAGUGUGCUUAAUGCCCUUAUGUAGAUCCAUAUUUCCAUCUGGUGUGGUUUUCCUUUUGCUGGAAAGAUUUCCUUUAACAUUUCUGGGAGUGUGAUUCUGCUGUGACGAAUACUUUGAGUUUUUGUAUAUCUGAAAAGUUUUUAUUUCGCCAUUGUUUUUAAAAGAAAUUUUGCUGUAUAUACAUUGACUUUUUUCUUUCAGUACUUUAAAGAUGUUCAGCUGUCUUCUCACUUGCAUUGUUUCUGAUGAGAAAUCUGCUUAAUUCUUAUCAUUGUUCCUUUGUAUGUAAUGUGUCUCAUUUCUCUCGCUUCUUUUAUGAUUUUCCUUUAAUCUCUGGUUUUGGGCACUUUGAUUAUGAUAGGCUUUGGUGGCAUUUUCUUCCUGUCUUGUGCUUUGAAUUUAUUGAGCUUCUUGGACCUCUGGACUUAUCGUUUGCAUCAAAUAUGGGCACUUUUUGGCCAUUAUUCAUAUAUUUUUCUGUCCCCUCCCUUCUCUUCUCCUUCAAGGGCUCCAAUUACACAUAUGUUAGGUUGCUUAAAGUUAUGUGAUAGCUCACUGAUGCUCUUUUAAUUCUUUUUGAUUGUUUUAUCUGUGUGUUUUAUUUUGGAUAGUGUCUAUUGCCAUGCCUUUAUGUUUAUUAGUCUUAACAGCAGUGUCUAGUCUGCCAUUAAUCUAUUCAAUGUAUUCUUUAUCUCACUCACAUAUUGUAGUUUUCCCCUCCAGAAUUUUGAUUUGAGUCUUUUUUAUAUCUUCUGUGUCUCUAAUUAACUUUUUGAACACAUGAAAUACAAUUGUAAUAGCUAUUUUUAUAUCUUUUUCUACUAAUGCUUAUAUCUAUGGCAAUUCUAGGUCAAUUUCAGUUCAGUGAUUAUUUUCUUCAUUAUGGGUGAUGUUUUCUUGUUUCUUUGUGUCUAGUGAUAUUUGAUUGGGUCUCUUUUACUUUGGUAGGUGCUGGAUAUUUUUAUGUUUUAUACAUCUUAUGUUUAUAUAAAACAAUGAGCUUUGUUCUGGAAUGUAGUUAAGUUGCUUGGAAACUGAUCCUUUAGGGUCUUACUCUUAUGAUUCAUUAGGCUUAACUAUAGCGCUGCUCAGUCUGUGGCUAAUUAUUUCUCAUCAUGGGGGCAAAACCUUUUUGAGUGCACUACUCAAUGCCCUGUGAAUUAAGAGUUUUCCCAUUUUGGCUGGUGGCAACAGGCAGUGUCUCCAGUGUUGACAACUCCGAUCCAAUAUCCGAGAAAUUGAGAAACUUUGUUUGAAAGUCCGAAAGGAUGACCUAGUACUUCUGAAGAGAAUGAUAGAUCCUGUUAAAGAAGAAGCAUCAGCAGCAACAGCAGAAUUUCUCCAACUCCAUUUGGAAUCUGUAGAAGAACUUAAGAAGCAAUUUAAUGAUGAAGAAACUUUGCUACAGCCUCCUUUGACCAGAUCCAUGACUGUUGGUGGAGCAUUUCAUACUACUGAAGCUGAAGCUAGUUCUCAGAGUUUGACUCAGAUAUAUGCCUUACCUGAAAUUCCUCAAGAUCAAAAUGCUGCAGAAUCGUGGGAAACCUUAGAAGCGGACUUAAUUGAACUUAGCCAACUGGUCACUGACUUCUCUCUCCUAGUGAAUUCUCAGCAGGAGAAGAUUGACAGCAUUGCAGACCAUGUCAACAGUGCUGCUGUGAAUGUUGAAGAGGGAACCAAAAACUUAGGGAAGGCUGCAAAAUACAAGCUGGCAGCUCUGCCUGUGGCAGGUGCACUCAUCGGGGGAAUGGUAGGGGGUCCUAUUGGCCUCCUUGCAGGCUUCAAAGUGGCAGGAAUUGCAGCUGCACUUGGUGGUGGGGUGUUGGGCUUCACAGGUGGAAAAUUGAUACAAAGAAAGAAACAGAAAAUGAUGGAGAAGCUCACUUCCAGCUGUCCAGAUCUUCCCAGCCAAACUGACAAGAAAUGCAGUUAAAAACCAAAUUUCAGUAUUAUUGGUGCCAACAUGUCUAUCCUGAGGACCUUUGCUGCUGUUGGACACUCCGUCACCUUUUGGAACACAAGUAUAUCAAGAUAGUGGCUACUGAUGUUCAAGUGGGAUUGAAGUGUGAUAAAUGGAUAUAUUUUGUUGUUUGCUGGGGUGUUCAUGGAGAUGUUAAGAGAUUGAGGCCCUGGGCUGAGGGUAUAUAAUGUAUGUCAGGUAAAGUUUGAAGACUGCCAAGGAGCAGAUUUUCUCCCUGGAAAUGUGAAAACUGAACCUAUAACUCUGAUAAGGACUUGAGAUGUGUAGAAACGUUGGGUUAUGGAAGACUAGUUUCUUCCAUAACCCUGAAUUGGAGACCUUAAUGCUAAGUGUAGAUUAUUGAGGUUUGUUAGUGAGGAAAAGAAUAAGAGUUCAGAAGCCUUUGUUAUCAGAUAGCGAAAUCAGGGCCUAGUGAGGAGCACAGGUCGACUACAUAAUGGAGUCCAUUGGCGAACCCUAUUGCAAUUUGGUCCAACUAUAUCUUCUGGUGAAGGAAAUUAAUGAUGUAAGAAAAUGCAAGAGGCUCAACUUCUCUUCCAAAAAUCUUCUGGCUUCUGAACUCUUCCUCUGCCUCUCUUUAAAUAAAUAACACAGAAUUUCAAGUGGUAGGAGACUUAUUAAGCCAGUCACCAAGCUUGGUCUGUCAGCCUGUCUUCUAACACCUCAAAGAUCUUGUGCCCUGUGCUGUCCCUCCCUUGUAAUUAUGAAAAGUUCUUUGGUUUCUGGGGUGAAUUCUACCCAUGUAUAAUGAGGAAUUCUCUCAUAACCUUUUUUGUCUUGUCUGUCAUCUCUGUUCAUCCCUUCCUAUAACCUCUAGGUAAAAAGAAAAGAAAAAAAGAAAUUUCGAGAUAUUUUCAACAUUGUUAGAGUUUGGGCUAAAAUGAGCAAGGAGAAAAAAACCACCAAGAACAUUUCCUGGGGCAUGUUCCAGUUUUGAGGGGUGAUAUAUCUGCCAGAUAGGGGGUAUCUGACCCAGUCUUCUUUUCAGCUGGUCUCUGGGGGGAGCUGAGAACUCGCUUGCUACCUCACAUCCUUUUCCCCAGACUUUUUAUCUCCUAUGCAUCCCUUUGCUUUCUAUAGCUGGUGUUUCUUCCCCAAAAUGGCGUUCCCAUGCUUACCUUUCUCACAUUCUAGACAAUGAUGGACAAAGACGCAUGCAAGACUCAGACCCGGGGAAUGGUGUGGUGCUAAUCUCAACACCUGACAUUCACAGCAAGCAUGGCCCAGCCCAACUGCAUGUCUAUCUCAAACCGCAGAAAGGCUUUAAUACUGGAAAAAAAGAAUUCAAGACUACAGGCAGCUCCCCUCUGUACCCCAACUCAUUUAAAAUAGGAGGAAUCACUUUUUGCCUUACUUAACGCUUUUUUCUGAGCACAGGGAUGGGCACCUGCACCCCAGAAGGUGUGAGCUGUCUCUCUGCCAGGAGCUAAGGUUCAUUAGGGGAUUGGAUGGUUUAUCACUUCUUUCUUUCUGAGUUUACUUUUAGUAACUUUUAUUGAUGGCUACCUUUCAUGUCCCUGUCUAAAGAGACUUUCUCUUUCAUACGUCUUAAAUCUCAUCAAUGAAAUCCAGUGAAACAGCACCAUUUCUUAGUAUCAUUAAAUAACUAGAAAGUAUCAAGUAUUGCUCUCUGCUGCUUUAUAUCAUUAACAUAUUAAUAAUACCAAGAAGGAAAUACUUUGAAUAAGUGUCAGAUUCUGAUCCAGUAUUGGACACCUGUGAUAUUGGACACCUGUGAGGCUGGGAUAAUUACUUUUGAAUUACACCUCUUCUCUAGUUUCUGGACCUUGCUCUGUCACUUUAACACAGGGUGAUCAAACCUGAAUGAGGAUCAGAACUCACCCAGGCACAUACUAAAGCAAGAUUCCUAAACCUCAGUUCCAGGGGUAAUUCUGACAUCACCCGUCCAGCAUAGUCAGCUGAAAUUAUAAAUCUAAGAAACAGUUACAUCAAGAUUCUGCUGUGUCAUUUAAUUCUGAAACUCCCAGUAUUCUACCCUUCUUCAUCACUGCAUAUUACCCCACUCUUCCAUCCCAAAUUGGCUAUCCUUUCAGCCCACCAACUUAGCGGCAGCACUAGGGAUUCAUUAUAAGGUAAAUCUGGUUUACAUAAAGACCUGAAGGAGGCCUGUAUUUGAAGCUCACACUUGGUAUUGGUAUCUCUCAUUUUUACUGAGCCAGUGUGGAAUACCACUGUAUGUACUCAUAUAAGCCCUUGACUUUUACUGCUCAUCAGGAUUGGAAUAUUACUCUAGCAGUCUUCACACAUAGGCAAGUUACAGUCCUUUUAAAAAGUAUCUCAUUUCCCUAUAAUGGAACCUAAUAGCCAACUUUUUCAUAGAAAUUGCUAGAAGAGUUUGAUCAACUAUAAAUGAUAAAGUGUUUAUAAGCAUAGUCAGUGUGACACAGAAACCAAUCUUAAAAUUGAAUUUAAUGUUUUAUCAUAUCAGAUUAAAUAUUUUCUCCAUGUCUUAUUUUUACUGCAACAAGUUAGAAAGUGGGAACACUUUGAUUAAUGUCUUAAAAUUUGUGGGCCCUCAUUUGGAUAAAGGCAGCAAUCCUAAGGACUUUUUUUUUUUUUUUAACAUAAUCUGAGAAUUUCUCUGUAGAGCAGAGACUUUCAAACCUUUUGGCUGUAACCCACAGUAAAAAACGCAUUUAUAUCAAACCUUAGAAUAUGUUUAAUGAACAAUACUUACCAUUCUGAUGCUUUUUAUUGUUUCAGUUUUUAAAAUAUGCCAGUUGCAACCCACUAAAUUGAUAUCUACCAAUGGGUUGCAACCCUUAGCUUGAAAAAAACACCCUCACAGAGGAACUGGUAUUUCUUGAAUACCUUCUGUUUGCCAGGCACUUCACCAGGCAUUUUACAAGUAAGGAAACUGGGCUUCAGAGAAAAUAAUUUGCAGAGGUUUACUCAACUACAAAGGGGUGAAGCCAGGAAUGUUAACUAGGUCUGUUGAGCUACAAAAACUUUUAUGUCUCUCAGACUAUACAGCCUCUAUACAAAAUUGAGAUGGGGGUUGGGGGCAGGGGCUCAUGCCUGCAAUCCCAGCACUUAGGGAGGCAGAGGCCAGAGGAUCACUUGAGCCCAGGAGUUUGAGACCAGCCUGGGCAACAUAGUGAGACUCUUGUCUGUAUGAAAAAAAUUAAGAAUUAGCUGGGUGUGGCAUAGCACACACCUGUGGUCCCAGCUACAUGGGAAGCUGAAGUGGGAGGAUCACUUGAACUCAGGAGCAGCCUUGGUGACAGAACAAGACCCUCUCUCAAAAAAAUAUUUAAAAAAAGGUGGGUCAUCCAUUCUCCUUUACCAAACAGGCUUUGAAAUGACACAUUCCAUUCAUUUGCAUCUUUUUAAAAAACUUCUGAUUCCUUACUGAGUGUCCAGCAGCCUCAAAGUUUUUAAUGGUAGCUGAUGCAGACAUAAACAGUGCUCAAUUUGGCCCUUAAACUAUAAAAUCAAGAAAGAGUAUUUCAAUCCCAUCCACCUGCCUGCAAGAUUUCUUAAUGUUCACUAGUUAUAACCAUUGUUUAAACAGUGCUUUUUGUGUAAUUUAAAAAUAAACUUUAAUGCUUUUUAAAACAAAUUUAUCAUAAUUCAUAGAUCAAAUGAUUAUCCUUUAAAAUGAUACCCUUGGGAAAUCAUGUACUUACUGUAGUGAUGCUAGUAUUAAUAUUACUUAGACCAAUUUUGAAACUGUUCUUUCAGAAUUGCCUCCAAAGACAUUUUGCAGAUCAUCCCAGAAAAGGGGGUAUGAUGGUGCUGUGUAGAACUGACCAGAGUUCCUGGAGGAUUUUGAGGUUAUACUGAAACUGAGUGCUGUACAGGGAGAAUUGCAUGAGUCCAGAAACUUCCUUCUGUGGGCUGCCUGCCUUCCUGCCCUCCCUUAAGUGCUCUAAGAUUUUUGUACAGGAGUAAGAAUCAAAUACUGGUAACAUCAAUCACAAGAAGUUGAGGAAACCUGUAAUAUAGCUAGAUAAUAUACAACGUUUGUCUUCCAUCAGAGUGCAGAAACCAAACCAUGCUUUGUGUUAACCUUAAAUAUGAAAGGUGUUUCUCAGGGUCCCCUUUGUCCUUCGUUGCUGCCAUAUGAAAUCUUACAAGGAAGGAUGAGGAAAAGCCUGGGGGGAGGUUCUCCUCGGAAAUGAGGUGGUUUUUUUUGUUAUUAAGUAGAACGUGGCUGUGGUUCACAGGUACUUAACGAAUGUUAGAUGAUGUUCUUAAGUAAUCAGAGGCCUAAUAAAAGGCAGGGGAGUUUCUCUUCUAGCCUAAAUUAAUAUUAAAAGUUCAGGGGUAUUUUUUGUUUUUAAAUUAAUACUUUAUUGUUUUUAACAGGUGGUUCUCAUAAUUUACAUUCAUUAAUUUGAUGCCCUUUUACAAAGAAACUUCUUAGGUAUUAUAAACCAUCAAUGUAAAGGAUCCACAUGGUAUGUAUCCACAUUGCUACUCUCAAAUAGAAAUGGGAGAUAAGAAAUAUAUCUGUGCAAUAUUAAAUUGAAAAAAAAAAACCCAUAAAAAGUGUCAAAGGCAAAUAAUUUGCUCUAGAUCACAAAACUAGUUAGCACAAGGCUAGGAUUAUAACCAGGGUCUAGGAAAAAAUCCUGAAGGUGAUUUAACUGAGUGUUAGGCCCUGUCAAGCCACCUGCUAAGGCUCAUGGUCUUUCAGACUAGCUUCAACAUUCCAAAUCAGGCAAUAGCUACAACGGAAAGAUAAUUGGACGGGGAAUCCUGAGAUCAGAGUCCUAGUUUGGCUUUGUCUCUUGUAGCAGGAUUUUUUAAAUCAGGGGCAGCUCUCUUCUCCCAUCCCAGCCAUGAAUCUUUCAACCUUAGUGGUCACCAACUUGACUCCAUUCCUUAUAUCAAGACUUGUCCUGUCAAUUCUCCCUUAAAUGUUAGUUGCAUCCAUUUCUAAAUAUAUCCAUGGCCAUCACCCUAGUAAAAAGACUAUUACCUCACACCCCGCACUUGAUCUUCCCCCAACUUUAAGUGACUCAGUUCCUUAUAUCACUGCCACAAGAAUUAACAACCAUGUCCAUCUUUCAUUUUUCUGCUGAAAGAUUUUCAGUGGUUCCCACUGAAUACCAAAUAAAGUUCGAAUCCCUUAGAUUGGCAUUCACAGCCUUCUACGUUCUGGCCCCAGCUUUAUCUCUUGAAACUCACUACUCACCAUCUGACAAUGCCACUAAAAAUCCACAAGAGUGAUUUUAAGGUUUUUCUAUGGUGAAGGUUCAAACUGGUAAUAAACCAUGUUUACAUUUUUCUGGUCUAAAAUAAUUUCUAUAUUACUUUAUAAUAGUCAGCUGGGGGUUAUUUAAGCUCUUGGACGAGCCUAAAACUUGUAUCCUGAAGAAAAUAUUUUUUUCCACCAGAAGAAAUUGCUUUCAAUUUCUUAACCUUCAAAACAAUGUCAGUGUUGUCACCUGUGCAUUUGAUAGCCACAGCACAAGUAUUCUUCAGGAGCAUAAAUCCUCCAGCCUUGAAUGGACCAUUGUCCAGCUCCUGUGAAAAACUUAAUAUUUGAGAAAGACAUUCAAUGGUACAUGUUUUCUGUACACUUCAUGAGUAGUUGAGAUUUUCUUGUAUUAAGGUUAAUCACUAAAAAGGUGUUUACUUGGGUUUCGUUAACUAAACCCCCUAAAGAUGUUUUCCAUUUUAUUGUUAAACACUUGGUGUUAGCAAGGGUCAGCACGAGAAAAGGCCCAAUGGCAAGAAUUUCUGCAAACUCUGUAAAGCUUACUGAAUUCAUUUGUCAUUUAUUACAUUGCUGAGUGGUGCUUGAAUAAGGAAACAUGCAAUAAAUUUACUUAUUUAACCAA